AGUUGGUGAAUGGCGUUGGUGGCGGGAAAGUUGAGUCUCUCCUGCGCCGAGCCUUCGGGGCGAUGUGUAGUGCCUUCCAUAGGGCUGAGUCUGGGACCGAGCUCCUUGCCCGACUUGAAGGUAGAAGUUCCUUGAAAGAAAUAGAACCAAAUCUGUUUGCUGAUGAAGAUUCACCUGUGCAUGGUGAUAUUCUUGAAUUUCAUGGCCCAGAAGGAACAGGAAAAACAGAAAUGCUUUAUCACCUAACAGCACGAUGUAUACUUCCCAAAUCAGAAGGUGGCCUGGAAGUAGAAGUCUUAUUUAUUGAUACAGAUUACCACUUUGAUAUGCUCCGGCUAGUUACAAUUCUUGAGCACAGACUAUCCCAAAGCUCUGAAGAAAUAAUCAAAUACUGCCUGGGAAGAUUUUUUUUGGUGUACUGCAGUAGUAGCACCCACUUACUUCUUACACUUUACUCACUAGAAAGUAUGUUUUGUAGUCACCCAUCUCUCUGCCUUUUGAUUUUGGAUAGCCUGUCAGCUUUUUACUGGAUAGACCGCGUCAAUGGAGGAGAAAGUGUGAACUUACAGGAGUCUACUCUGAGGAAAUGUUCUCAGUGCUUAGAGAAGCUUGUAAAUGACUAUCGCCUGGUUCUUUUUGCAACGACACAAACUAUAAUGCAGAAAGCCUCGAGCUCAUCAGAAGAACCUUCUCAUGCCUCUCGACGACUGUGUGAUGUGGACAUAGACUACAGACCUUAUCUCUGUAAGGCAUGGCAGCAACUGGUGAAGCACAGGAUGUUUUUCUCCAAACAAGAUGAUUCUCAAAGCAGCAACCAAUUUUCAUUAGUUUCACGUUGUUUAAAAAGUAACAGUUUAAAAAAACAUUUUUUUAUUAUUGGAGAAAGUGGGGUUGAAUUUUGUUGAUAUACAUCAUAAAAUAGUCUUUUGCAGGGUACUACGCAAGCCUUAAAAUUUUUCUUAAGACAGAGUCUUGCUCUGUCUCCCAGGCUGGAGUGCAGUGGCACAAUCAUGGCUCACUGCAGCCUUGAACUCCUGGCCUCAAGGGAUCCUCCUAUGUGUGCCUCCUAGAGUGCAGGGAUUACAGGCGUGAGCCACUGCUCGUGGCCAAAAGUUUUCUUUUUUUUUUUUUUUCUUUUUGAAACAGUCUUACUCUGUCUCCCAGGCUGCUGGAGUGCAGUGGCACAAUCUCGGCCCGCUGCAGCCUCUGCCUCUUGGGUUCAAGUGAUUCUUCCACCUCAGCCUCCCAGGUAGCUGGGAUUACAGGCACCCACCACCACGCCUGGCUAAUUUUUGUAUUUUUAAUAGAGACGGGGUUUCACCAUGUUGGCCAGGCUGGUCUCGAACUCCUGACCUCAAGUGAUCCACCCACCUCGGCCUCCCAAAGUGCUAGGAUUACAGGCCCGUGCCCAGCCCUAAAGUUUUAAACUCUAGGGGAAUUAACAGUAUUUCUUUACAGAAUGGAUUUGUUAAACUAGCACAGUAAAAGUAAAGACUAUUCUGUUUCUAGGCUGUUGAAUCAAAGUGAUUUUAGCAAUUAAACUUUGUAUUAAUUUACCACCAAUAUUUCUUCACAAAGGAACUUUUAAAAGAUUAUCUCAGAAAGUAAAUCUGAGAGGUAAGAAGUAAUAAUGAGUAAAUGGUAAGUACUUGAGUAAAUCUAAAGAAAUAUUGAUAGUAAGGCAAUCCUAAGCAAAAAGAACAAAGCUGGAGGCAUCACGCUACCCAGCUUCAAACUAUACUACAAGGCUACAGUAACCAAAACAGCAUAGUACUGGCACAAAAACACACGUAGACUGAUGGAACAGAAUAGAGAAUUUAGAAAUGAGACCACACACCUAUAAUUUUUUUGAUCUUCGAUGAACCUGACAAAAACAAGCAAUGGGCAAUGGAUUCUCUAUUCAAUAAAUCGUGCUGGGAUAACUGGCCAGCCAUAUGGAAAAGAUUGAAAAUGGACGCCUUCCUUAUGCCAUAUACAAAAAUUAACUCAAGAUGGAUUAAAGACUUAAUGUAAAACCCAAAACAGUAAAAAUCCUGGAAGACAACCCAGGCAGUACCAUUCAGGACAUAGGCACAGGCAAAGAUUUCAUGACGAAGACGCCAAAAACAAUUGCAACAGAAGCAAAAAUUCACAAAUGGGAUCUAAUUAAACUAAAGAGCUGCACAGCAAAAGAAACUAUCAAGAGAGUAAACAGACAGCUUACAGAAUGGGAGAAAAUUGUUGCAAACUAUGCAUCUGAGAAAGGUCUGAAAUCCAGCAUCUAUACGUAAUUUAAACAAAUUUAGAAGAAAAAACCACCCCAUUAAAAAGUGGGCAAAGGACAUGAACAGACACUUUUCAAAAGAAGACAUCUGUGGCCAACAAUCCUAUGGAAAAAAGCCCAGCAUCACUGAUCAUUAGAGAAAUGCAAAUCGAAACAACAACGAGAUACCAUCUCACACCAGUCCAAAUGGCUAUUAUAAAAAUGUCAGAAAAUAACAGAUGCUGGUGAGGUUGUGGAGAAAAAGAUAUGCUUAUACACUGUUGGUGGAAAUGUAAAUUAAAUUAGUUCAGCCAUUGUGGAAGACAGUGUGGGGAUAAAGACAGAGAUACCAUUCAACCCAGCAAUCUCAUUACUGGGUAUAUACCCAAAGGAAUAGAAAUCAUUGUUAUAAAGACACAUGCACGCGUAUGUUCGUUGCAGCACUGCCCAUCAGUGACAGACUGGAUUAAAAAAAUGUGGUACAUACACACCAGGGAAUACUAUACAGCCAUAAAAAGGAACAAGACUGACUGGGCGUGGUGGCUCAUGCCUGUGAUCCUAGCACUUUGCGAGGCCGAGGUGGGUGGAUUGCCCGCGCUCAGGAGGUCAAGACCAGCCUGGGCAACACGGUGAAACCCCAUCUCUAUUAAAAUACAAAAAAUUAGCUGGGCAUGGUGGUGCGUGCCUGUAGUGCCAGCUACUCAGGAGGCCGAGGCAGGAGAAUUGCUGGAACCCAGGAGGUGGAGGUUGCAGUGAGCUGAGAUCGCGCCAUUGCACUCCCGCCUGGGCGACUCCAUCUCUAAAAAAUAAAAAAUAAAAUAUAAGGAACAAGAUCAUACCUUUGCCAGGGACAUGGAUGGAGCUGGACGCUAUUAUCCUUAGCAAACUAACAUAGGAACAGAAAACCAGAUACUGCAUGUUUUCACUUAUAAGUGGGAGCUAAAUGAUGAGAACUCCUGGAUACAAAGAAGGGAACAACACACACACACACACACACACACACCCUCUCACAGACUUAGAAUACGUGGCAAGAAAAGCAUAUAAUUUGACAUUAGGAGCAGAAGAAUUAGUGUGCUAAGGUCCUUGCAUUGUCCGGGAGAAGGGGAAAAGUAUCAACAUUAGACAUUGAUAAAGGGUCUGCACCUUUUGAUUUCUUAACCACUCAAGGAUAGAAAAGGGGCAUAACUUUAAAAUGAAACAGGAAAAUGGUGGGCUGAUUUUUAAAUUUAAAAGAACCGAAUACAGCAGGACAGAUCCAAAGCACAGAGGAGAUGGUGUAUUUAACUCCAUCCACACCAAUCAUUACAUUACAUGCAAAGGGACUGAGGACUCCAGUUAAAAUGACAGUUUUAGGCUGGUUUUUAAAAUACAUAUUUGCUGUUUUAUUUUUAGAGACAAGGUCUCGCUCCGUUGCCCAGGCUGGAGUGCAGUGGCAUCAUAACUCACUGCAGCCUCGAACUCCUGGGUUCCAGUGAGCCUCCACCUCAGCCUCCAAAGUAGCUGUGAUUACAGGUGUGUGCCACCUUGCCUAGCUGAGUCCCUUGAAUUGAUAAAAGGUAUAUACAAAAAUCCCUCAGUAAACAUUAGUUAAUAGUGAAAUAUUAGAAGUGUCUCUUUUAAAAUCAAGAACAAGAGUGCCUGCUAUUACUACUUGUAUUCAACAUUGUACUGAAAGUGUCAACACAGUAAAGCAAGGAAAAUGAAAAAGCAUGAAAAAAAGGCAUAUGGAAGAAACAAAACUGUCAUUCUUUAAAGGUUAGAUGAUUGUAUGUAUGGAAAUCCAAUAUCAUCUAUAAGCAGAUUAUUAGAAUUAAGAGUUUAGCAAAUUUGCGAGCUAAAACAUCAACAUUUAAGUUUUUCUAAGUACCAGCAACAGAAUUAAAAAAUAGAAUUUUAGGCUGAGUGCAGUGGCUCACAACUGUAAUCCCAGCACUUUGGGAGGCCAAGGAGGGAGGAUUGCUUGAGUCCUAGGAGUUCAAGACCAGCCUGGGCAACAUAGUGUAAGACCCUGUCUCUAUAAAAAUAAAUUUUAAAAAAGAAAAUGGAAUUUUAAAUAUAUAUAAUAUUUAAUCAUAACUAAAAAUAUAAAGUUUCUAGAAAUAAAUCUAAUAAAAAUAUGCAAGACCUUUUUGGAGAAAAUUACAAAGCUUUAUUGUAAGAAGCAGAGUUUAACCCUUUUCCCAUUUAGAAAAAAAAAGUGCAGCUCACUGCCAGCGCUCAUUUAAUUUUACGUAAACACACUCUUGGAGGCUGAAGCAAAUCUUACUGAUUUUCAAUGUGAAAAUAAAAUAUAAAAACUAUUCUUGGAGUUAUUUCUAAACAGAACUAACAUCAGAAUCAUCUGAAUCAUCAGAAUCAUCUCUUUCAGAAAAAUCGGACUCAUCGAAUGAAUCUUCGGCUAACUGUUGAGAACGAUGUUAACAUCACGUGUAGGAAUACUACAUUUUCCAGGAUUUGACAUUUUCAGCGAUCAAGAAUUACUAUGUUUUGUAAAUGGAAAUACCACUACUAAAGACAGAAUGCUAUAAA